CAUCUGUGUUUGUAUUGGAAGCAGUUGUUUGGCCUUGCUGAGCAAACGUCUAUGCCUUCUCCAUUACAUCCAAAGGAGAAUAGCCCCAUGUGAAGAAUGGAAUCAGUAGAUGUUUGGUCGCUGUACCAUAUCCACUCCUAGGAUACAACAAGAGCAAGCCCAAUUCUCUUGGUGGUGUGGGCAGUCGGCUUGCACCACGUACCUAUCUCAGCUCUUUUUGGAAGCUUAUGUCCUCCCCACAACUUCCAGCUUUCUUAUGGGACAAGGGUACACUCACCACUGCCAUAUCUAAUCCUGCUUGCCUGGUAAAUGUUCUCUUCUUCUUUACACCCCUGAUGACUCUGGUCACUCUACUCAUCCUGGUCUGGAAAGUAACCAAAGACAAAAGCAACAAGAACAGAGAGACACACCCAAGAAAGGAGGCAACAUGGCUGCCAUAAAGAUCUGGAUCUCUUGGUGGGGACUCCACUGAGGUGAAGACCUGAUUGUACAAGAGAGGCACGGCCACUGGAGCUGUCUCAGAGCCCAGAGCCAGGGGAGCCAGAGCUGCUUUAGCCACCCUGUUCCUCCAUUGCCAGAUGUCCCCCCAGGCCUCAUUUCCUUCCUCUGCCACCAUCCCUCUUAUAAUGCACUCCUCCUGCGGUUCUUUGGCUUGUCCCAGCUUCUGAGUUUGAAUGUCUUUUUUUUUUUUUUUUUUUUUGUGGAUCUUCAAGACUGAAAUAGUAAAUGGCUCUUGAUUUCUGCACUAACAGAGGAAAGAAACAAGUACAUGGAAAAGUAAAAAUUGAUUACAAAGCCUAAAUUUUCCUCUAUAAAUUGGGCAUGUGCUGACUGUGGGAUAUUGAAAUUAUUGGGAGCUCACAGCAUCUCAAGUUAUAUAAUGAAGCUAUUCUGGAAGCUCAUUUCCAGAAGAUCCUUAAAAUGAAAUGGCUCACUCUCUGCUGAAUUGUAGGUACACUCUUUCCUCCUCUUCACUUAAUGCUGGGAGUAAAAUGUAUUUUUUUUAUUAAGAAAU